AUGACAGGGUCUUUGUCAGGGACUCUCAGAGCCCCAAUCAAGCUCAGGGAGCACCUUCUUGGCAGCAGCCCCACGAAGGCAGAAGAGGGCCCAGGCCUGUCCCUGCCUGCUGAAGGAGCAAAGACAGGAGCAAAGGGAAGCAGCCUUCACCGAAGGGUCCUUCCCCAAGGUGCGCAGAAGCAGCGGCACUUACCCAGGGGCAUUCUCACCCCGCGGACAGUGGAAGCCCCUCAGGGGGUGCAGAUCAGAGUGCUGCAGGAGAGAGAGGGCGCUGGCUGGUGCGAAGCCGUCCGAGGCAACAGUCAAGUGGCUUUGGAGGCUUCCAAUGCCAGGAGUCGGGGGCGGGCAGCUAAAGUCGCCGAGCCCUGUUUCCCGCCAUCCAGGGGCACUAAGCCUCCCCGCAGAGUAGCUGCGCGGACAGGGGGUCUGACGACCGCACGUGGCCCGCUCAGCACUGCCGCGGCCAAGGGCGCGACUCACCUGCCAGUGUCUUUCCCGAGGACACGCGAAUCCUGGGGGGCUCACUCCGGCAAAGAGGACGAGACACUGCACCAAGGACAGGGCCUGACCUCUCUGGCCGCCUUCCCCGGGGCCUCAGUUUCCCCCGAUGGUGAGAGUGGAGCCGACCAUGCGCCCUGCUGUGGACUCACCCGGCGCCCUGGCGUCGAGUGGCGGCGGAGACCUGACAGACAGCGUGGGAAAAAUCAAGAUGUCUGCAGAUUUCGAGAGAUGGGGUGCGGUGGCGUGCGAUGGCGAAGGACGGCGAGGGACGGCGAAGGACUGAGGCCACACGACAAGGAAGCUACGCUCGUUUCGCGCCGGCGGAAAUACAGACGAGAGCGCGAGCUGCGGCCUAGAGCGGUAGGAACCGACGCGAGCAGUCCUGCAGCGUCCCCUGGCGGAGCGGAGGCUCAACGCCAGACUCUGGAGGACUUGGGAUAAUUUUCGAAAACUAUCUGGAAGUUUAGAAGUAAACUUCUCCCACUUGCUUUGCUUUUCUGUUUGUUCUGAAGAUGUUCCUUGGUCACUGAUUCAUUAUUAAUCUGUAGGAAUGGCCAAUUUUCCAUGAUAGGAGCUGUUACUACGAUGAGGGGACUGUGCUUAGUUUGGACUUCUUUCUGCAAGGGUCCAAAGGCAUCUGUCUUUGAUUCACCACUGUACUCAGUACCUAGUUCAGUGACUAGCACAGUUGAAUGAAUGAAUUCUACCCCCGCCCCAUUCCUUUUUUUCUGAACAAUGUCAGACCGAGAUGACUGAGUCAUGGCCUGAGACUGGAAUGUGAGCGUGAGAAGAUGAGCCAAGAGAGAUGCACAGCGGGUAACUGCUUUGCUAAACUCCAGCCUCAAAGUACACGGGAUGGAGGGUGGAAAGAGUCUCUGAAGCAGAAGAGACCUGACCAGACUGGCAUCUGAGGAACCUGAUCAGAUUUGCACAGUGACAGAGACUGUAGACAGAUGUCCCAUGUUCCCUGCAACAUACUGGAGACAAUCUUGGGAGGGGACUCAUGGCCCACAAAUCCUCAUAAGCAUUGGCACUGCCUGCACCCUGGGCAGGAUGUGCCUCUUCGGCCUGAGACAGCCCUGCUACUGACUCUGCCCAUGUUCUGGAGUGCAAGCAGCCCACCCUUGGGCCUGAUGAGGAGCCCACGCCCCACCCUCCGCCCCGCUCCAGUCAGAUUCUUGGUACUCAAUAGGUCAGAAGGACAAGAAAAUCCAGUCCUGAUCUAUGCAACCAUGAGGGAAAUGGGGGUCCCUGAGGUGAGAUCUGCUCCAUAUUUUGUACCUGGGAGAGGCCCAUGGGAUUCCCAGACUGUGAGAACACUGGGAGUCUCUGUGAUGGGGAGGGGCUGUGGGAUGCUGCUAUGGUUUGGCUGUGACCCCACCUAAAUCUCAUCUGGAACUGUACUUCCCAUAAUUCCCACCUGUCGUGGGAGGUAAUGGAAUCAUGGGGGUGGUUACCCCCAUGCUGCGGUUCUUCUGAUAGUGAGUGAGUUCUCAUGAGACCUGAUGGUUUUAUAAGGGGCUUUACCCACUUUUGCUCUAUACUUCUCCUUGCUGCCACCAUGUGAAGAAAGACAUGUUUGCUUCCACUUCCGCCAUGAUUGUAAGUUUCCUGAGGCCUCCACAGCCAUGCUGAACUGUGAGUCAAUUAAACCUCUUUCCUUCAUGAA